CUUCCACGUAUUCGCGGAUGAUGUGCACCGUUGUCACCUCCGCCUUGGAAGGAGGAACAAUGACAACUCGAUGCAACUUGCUGGAUUAAGAUAGAAACAAGUUGGGUGCUGAGAAAUUCAGUCUAUUUGGGUUUAUUGGACCCGGGUCUGGAACAGUAACUUAACGAUUUAUUAAGUGGUGGAACUUUCGGAAUACUGGGGAGGUGAACAUGUGUUCUUUGAAGUUAAUUUUUAAGAAUUUGCCAAAUGAAAUUUACCUGGAGUGGGGGGAGUUUUCCUUAGAAUAGAGGGCAGGUGAAUUAAUUUGAUUGAUUGUGGUUCUUUGUGAUGUGGACCUUUUUCGAUUUAAACCAGUUUGAUAUAAAGUGUAGUUGAGGAUGGCCAUACAGGUCUGAACUUUGCUGUGUAGGAUCUUUAGAGGAAGCAGUUGCCAGCUAUAACUUUUUUCCUUUAGUCUUUAAUAUUGAGAACACGCCUAUAAUAUUGAUAAUUAGUAGUAAAAAGAAGUAUUUUCAAAAGAGGAGGAAACCAUUUUUACCUGAAAUAAUUACAGAUAAUGUGUGCAUGUUGAAAUACAUAAAUUGCCGCUUGCUGUAAAUACAGAUUUAUUGUGUAUCUGAAGGUUUAGCAAUUUGAACCAGAGGUGUGGCCCUGUCCCUCUUGGAGCGCCUUAUAUUCCCAGGUUAGAGUCCACAAACGCUCUAAUCCCGGCUUGUGUGGGAACUCCAGCCCAUUUUUCACUUUGUAAUCUCUAAACAUUCGACAUUCUGGUCCCUCUCCCAAGCUCUGGCUCCAAUAGCUUCCCAUACCUGGUCCCUGUCGGCCGUGCCCUGCCCGGCAUUCCUCCACCCCUUUUCUCCACCCCGUACACUCUUGUCCUUCAGAAAGGCCCCGUGAGAAUGUUGCUUCCUGGUGAAACCUUCACACACACAGCCGUUGGGGUGGUUACUCGAGAGAACAUUGAAAGUAUUCUCUAAGCUAUUUGAAGAGAGUGACUAAAUGCACCUGGGUCAGGCUGUCUGUGGGUAUGAAGUGGUUGGGAGAAUCCAAGAACAUGGUGGUGAAUGGCAGGAGAAAUGGAGGCAAGUUGUCUAAUGACCAUCAGCAGAAUCAAUCAAAAUUACAGCACACGGGGAAGGACACCCUGAAGGCUGGCAAAAAUGCAGUCGAGAGGAGGUCGAACAGAUGUAAUGGUAACUCGGGAUUUGAAGGACAGAGUCGCUAUGUACCAUCCUCUGGAAUGUCCGCCAAGGAACUCUGUGAAAAUGAUGACCUAGCAACCAGUUUGGUUCUUGAUCCCUAUUUAGGUUUUCAAACACACAAAAUGAAUACUAGCGCCUUUCCUUCGAGGAGCUCAAGGCAUUUUUCAAAAUCUGACAGUUUUUCUCACAACAACCCUGUGAGAUUUAGGCCUAUUAAAGGAAGGCAGGAAGAACUAAAGGAAGUAAUUGAACGUUUUAAGAAAGAUGAACACUUGGAGAAAGCCUUCAAAUGUUUGACUUCAGGCGAAUGGGCACGGCACUAUUUUCUCAACAAGAAUAAAAUGCAGGAGAAAUUAUUCAAAGAACAUGUAUUUAUUUAUUUGCGAAUGUUUGCAACUGACAGUGGAUUUGAAAUAUUGCCAUGUAAUAGAUACUCAUCAGAACAAAAUGGAGCCAAAAUAGUUGCAACAAAAGAGUGGAAACGAAAUGACAAAAUAGAAUUACUGGUGGGUUGUAUUGCCGAACUUUCAGAAAUUGAGGAGAACAUGCUACUUAGACAUGGAGAAAACGACUUCAGUGUCAUGUACUCCACAAGGAAAAACUGUGCUCAACUCUGGCUGGGUCCUGCUGCGUUUAUAAACCAUGAUUGCAGACCUAAUUGUAAGUUUGUGUCAACUGGUCGAGAUACAGCAUGUGUGAAGGCUCUAAGAGACAUUGAACCUGGAGAAGAAAUUUCUUGUUAUUAUGGAGAUGGGUUCUUUGGAGAAAAUAAUGAGUUCUGCGAGUGUUACACUUGCGAAAGACGGGGCACUGGUGCUUUUAAAUCCAGAGUGGGACUGCCUGCGCCUGCUCCUGUUAUCAAUAGCAAAUAUGGACUCAGAGAAACAGAUAAACGUUUAAAUAGGCUUAAAAAGUUAGGUGACAGCAGCAAAAAUUCAGACAGUCAAUCUGUCAGCUCUAACACUGAUGCAGAUACCACUCAGGAAAAAAACAAUGCAACUUCUAACCGAAAAUCUUCAGUUGGCGUAAAAAAGAAUAGCAAGAGCAGAACGUUAACGAGGCAAUCUAUGUCAAGAAUUCCAGCUUCUUCCAACUCUACCUCAUCUAAGCUAACUCAUAUAAAUAAUUCCAGGGUACCAAAGAAACUGAAGAAGCCUGCAAAGCCUUUACUUUCAAAGAUAAAAUUGAGAAAUCAUUGCAAGCGGCUGGAGCAAAAGAAUGCUUCAAGAAAACUCGAAAUGGGAAACUUAGUACUGAAAGAGCCUAAAGUAGUUCUGUAUAAAAAUUUGCCCAUUAAAAAAGAUAAGGAGCCAGAGGGACCAGCCCAAGCCGCAGUUGCCAGCGGGUGCUUGACUAGACACGCGGCGAGAGAACACAGACAGAAUCCUGUGAGAGGUGCUCAUUCGCAGGGGGAGAGCUCGCCCUGCACCUACAUAACUCGGCGGUCAGUGAGGACAAGAACAAAUCUGAAGGAGGCCUCUGACAUCAAGCUUGAACCAAAUACGUUGAAUGGCUAUAAAAGCAGUGUGACGGAACCUUGCCCCGACAGUGGUGAACAGCUGCAGCCAGCUCCUGUGCUGCAGGAGGAAGAACUGGCUCAUGAGACUGCACAAAAAGGGGAGGCAAAGUGUCAUAAGAGUGACACAGGCAUGUCCAAAAAGAAGUCACGACAAGGAAAACUUGUGAAACAGUUUGCAAAAAUAGAGGAAUCUACUCCAGUGCACGAUUCUCCUGGAAAAGACGACGCGGUACCAGAUUUGAUGGGUCCCCAUUCUGACCAGGGUGAGCACAGUGGCACUGUGGGCGUGCCUGUGAGCUACACAGACUGUGCUCCUUCACCCGUCGGUUGUUCAGUUGUGACAUCAGAUAGCUUCAAAACAAAAGACAGCUUUAGAACUGCAAAAAGUAAAAAGAAGAGGCGAAUCACAAGGUAUGAUGCACAGUUAAUCCUAGAAAAUAACUCUGGGAUUCCCAAAUUGACUCUUCGUAGGCGUCAUGAUAGCAGCAGCAAAACAAAUGACCAAGAGAAUGAUGGAAUGAACUCUUCCAAAAUAAGCAUCAAGUUAAGCAAAGACCAUGACAACGAUAACAAUCUCUAUGUAGCAAAGCUUAAUAAUGGAUUUAACUCAGGAUCAGGCAGUAGUUCUACAAAAUUAAAAAUCCAGCUAAAACGAGAUGAGGAAAAUAGGGGGUCUUAUACAGAGGGGCUUCAUGAAAAUGGGGUGUGCUGCAGUGAUCCUCUUUCUCUCUUGGAGUCUCGAAUGGAGGUGGAUGACUAUAGUCAGUAUGAGGAAGAAAGUACAGAUGAUUCCUCCUCUUCUGAGGGCGAUGAAGAGGAGGAUGACUAUGAUGAUGACUUUGAAGACGAUUUUAUUCCUCUUCCUCCAGCUAAGCGCUUGAGGUUAAUAGUUGGAAAAGACUCUAUAGAUAUUGACAUUUCUUCAAGGAGAAGAGAAGAUCAGUCUUUAAGGCUUAAUGCCUAAGCUCUUGGUCUUAACUUGACCUGGGAUAACUACUUUAAAGAAAUAAAAAAUUCCAGUCAAUUAUUCCUCAACUGAAAGUUUAGUGGCAGCACUUCUAUUGUCCCUUCACUUAUCAGCAUACUAUUGUAGAAAGUGUACAGCAUACUGACUCAAUUCUUAAGUCUGAUUUGUGCAAAUUUUUAUCGUACUUUUUAAAUAGCCUUCUUACGUGCAAUUCUGAGUUAGAGGUAAAGCCCUGUUGUAAAAUAAAGGCUCAAGCAAAAUUGUACAGUGAUAGCAACUUUCCACACAGGACGUUGAAAACAGUAAUGUGGCUACACAGUUUUUUUAACUGUAAGAGCAUCAGCUGGCUCUUUAAUAUAUGACUAAACAAUAAUUUAAAACAAAUCAUAGUAGCAGCAUAUUAAGGGUUUCUAGUAUGCUAAUAUCACCAGCAAUGAUCUUUGGCUUUUUGAUUUAUUUGCUAGAUGUUUCCCCCUUGGAGUUUUGUCAGUUUCACACUGUUUGCUGGCCCAGGUGUACUGUUUGUGGCCUUUGUUAAUAUCGCAAACCAUUGGUUGGGAGUCAGAUUGGUUUCUUAAAAAAAAAAAAAAAAUGACAUACGUGACAGCUCACUUUUCAGUUCAUUAUAUGUACGAGGGUAGCAGUGUGUGGGAUGAGGUUCGAUACAGCGUAUUUAUUGCUUGUCAUGUAAAUUAAAAACCUUGUAUUUAACUCUUUUCAAUCCUUUUAGAUAAAAUUGUUCUUUGCAAGAAUGAUUGGUGCUUAUUUUUUCAAAAAUUUGCUGUGAACAACGUGAUGACAACAAGCAACAUUUAUCUAAUGAACUACAGCUAUCUUAAUUUGGUUCUUCAAGUUUUCUGUUGCACUUGUAAAAUGCUACAAGGAAUAUUAAAAAAAUCUAUUCACUUUAACUUAUAAUAGUUUAUGAAAUAAAAACAUGAGUCACAGCUUUUGUUCUGUGGUAACCUAUAAAAAAAGUUUGUCUUUGAGAUUCAAUGUAAAGAACUGAAAACAAUGUAUAUGUUGUAAAUAUUUGUGUGUUGUGAGAAAUUUUUGUCAUAAGAAAUUAAAAGAACUUACCAGGAAGGUUUUUAAGUUUAGAAAUAUUCAUGCCAAUAAAAUAGGAAAUUAUAAAUAUAUAGUUUUAAGCACUGCAUCAGUGGGAGUUCUUGGCUUAUGUUAGUUUAUGUUAGUUUAUUAUGAAAACAUCAAAGAUUUUUUUGACUAUAUUAUCAGUUAAACAAAAAGGAGUCAGAUUUAAUUUGUUUUUUGAAGCACUUUGAGAAAUUAAUUUUAAUUAACUUAAUGAGCAAAUUUUUAUUACUACUUUAUGUUCAAUACCAGGUUCUUUUCAUUUCUCUGGAUUAUUUUGCAAAUCAUUGGACAGAGAAUUUGGGAAUAUAAAUCUGUAACAGGUGUUUGACACCAGUAGGUCUCUUUAUUUCUGGGAAAUGUGUACCUGUACUUUCUGAUAUACAGUGUUCCUAAGUAAAAAUCAAUUCAGGGGAUUUGUAUAGUGUCUAUAGGAAAGUAGCCCAUGUCUUGAAAUAUGAAAAGGAAUCUGAAGGUCAUGAAAAGUCCAGUGGAGAAAAUCUCAAUGCUUACUGUUACUACUAAUUGAUUCCUACUAGUUUCCAGGUUUGGGGGGAUAUUGUUUCAAUGACGCUCCUUAAGACUGUUGAUUGCCCAUAGGUUCCAAAUAGAAAUUAAGACUCAUGAACAUUUUUAGAAAGUAGAUUGUUUUCUCCUGGUUCUCUAAGGAACUACUUCUGCAGUCUUACAUAGUCUCAUCCUUGUUUGUUGUGGUGCAGUCGAACUCCUCAGGCGUUUGGAAAGCAUGUGGUAGACCUUCUUCCACACCCACCCAUACCCCCGUUCACUGCGUCUGGAGGUCUUCAACAGUGAAGUAGGGCAGCCCACACAGCCUCUCAGGAGCACCUGUCCGAGGCACCCGGAGCACUUUGCAGAGCACGUCCAGCCCUCAUGGGGUCCCUGCAUAGAAAUGUGAACCCCUGCCACUGAGGAAGAUGAAGGUAGACCCUGUGUCUGGAGGUGCUGGAGGGCAGCGGGUCACCUCUUGUAUUCCCACCUUAGUUUGGGGUGUUUUGAAGAGGUUCAGAGACUAAAUCUUAAACCUUAUUUGAAUACCAACGAUAGCUAUUUUGGGAAUUUCGAUCUUAAAAAGUGACAAAACACAUUUCCCAUUUUCAUUUUUCAGCUGAAUUUUAGUAACUUAUUUUUGAUGUUUUAAUUUUAUCAUGGCCUCCUCUUUGGAGGCCAACCUUCCCAUGGGUCUCAAAGCAGUGACAUUUGGUAGUAAAUCACUGCCUCUCAGGAGUCGGUAUGCACAAGCACUCAGCAGCCACUGUUGAUGCCUUCUAGGGAAACCUAAUUUCCGUUGGUAAAGGUAGGGGCCUCGGAACUGUUCCGGAUCUGCUGUAGAACUUCACCGUGUGGAAUGGUGACAGCCACACACCGUUGACCAGUUUAGAAGAGGUUGCAUUCAAUAAAACUCUUAGCUUGAGCUUAUGCAAUGAUUGGUUAAGAUUUUGGCAUUGUAAGAAUUAGGAGAUGAUCAUAGAAAUAUAUGUAAAGUAUUCAAUUUUCAAUCAUUUUCAAAUUACUGUUAUAAAUUGUUUUUGCUGAGUUGUAAUACUUUUGAGAUACAAUGUAUUCCUUGUACUGAAAGAAUGAAAAAGGACUUUUUCAGCAUUUGAGGUAAGUUCUUUAACGUUUCAUUAAAAACAUUUUUUACAAAUAUUUUGUACAUGCACUUGCAGUAUUGAGGUUAAUCAUUUUAAUAAAUUCGGAAAUUAAAACAA